GUUCGGACACCGCCCCCCGCCCCCGCCGGACGGUCCCGCCCCGCGCGCCCCCCGCUCCCGCCCCGCGCGCCGCCGGAGUUCCGCGGAGUUGACCGGGUCGGCGCCGUCGGUCCUGAGCGCUGCCUUCCGCGUUCCGCCGCGGCCCCACCUGGAGCCCCCGCCCCGCGCCAUGGCCGGAGCUCCCGGGGCGCAGCGCUGACGGCGGCGGGGGGAGCGCGCCAUGCCCAGCAGGACCGGCCCCAAGAUGGAAGGGAGCGGCGGCCGCGUCCGCCUCAAGGCGCAUUACGGGGGGGACAUCUUCAUCACCAGCGUGGACGCCGCCACGACCUUCGAGGAGCUCUGUGAGGAAGUGAGAGACAUGUGUCGUCUGCACCAGCAGCACCCGCUCACCCUCAAGUGGGUGGACAGCGAAGGUGACCCUUGCACGGUGUCCUCCCAGAUGGAGCUGGAAGAGGCUUUCCGCCUGGCCCGUCAGUGCAGGGAUGAAGGCCUCAUCAUUCAUGUUUUCCCGAGCACCCCUGAGCAGCCUGGCCUGCCAUGUCCGGGAGAAGACAAAUCUAUCUACCGCCGGGGAGCCAGAAGAUGGAGGAAGCUGUACCGUGCCAACGGCCACCUCUUCCAAGCCAAGCGCUUUAACAGGAGAGCGUACUGCGGUCAGUGCAGCGAGAGGAUAUGGGGCCUCGCGAGGCAAGGCUACAGGUGCAUCAACUGCAAACUGCUGGUCCAUAAGCGCUGCCACGGCCUCGUCCCGCUGACCUGCAGGAAGCAUAUGGAUUCUGUCAUGCCUUCCCAAGAGCCUCCAGUAGACGACAAGAACGAGGACGCCGACCUUCCUUCCGAGGAGACAGAUGGAAUUGCUUACAUUUCCUCAUCCCGGAAGCAUGACAGCAUUAAAGACGACUCGGAGGACCUUAAGCCAGUUAUCGAUGGGAUGGAUGGAAUCAAAAUCUCUCAGGGGCUUGGGCUGCAGGACUUUGACCUAAUCAGAGUCAUCGGGCGCGGGAGCUACGCCAAGGUUCUCCUGGUGCGGUUGAAGAAGAAUGACCAAAUUUACGCCAUGAAAGUGGUGAAGAAAGAGCUGGUGCAUGAUGACGAGGAUAUUGACUGGGUACAGACAGAGAAGCACGUGUUUGAGCAGGCAUCCAGCAACCCCUUCCUGGUCGGAUUACACUCCUGCUUCCAGACGACAAGUCGCCUCCGGCGCCUCUCUCCCUGCAGGUUGUUCCUGGUCAUUGAGUACGUCAACGGCGGGGACCUGAUGUUCCACAUGCAGAGGCAGAGGAAGCUCCCUGAGGAGCACGCCAGGUUCUACGCGGCCGAGAUCUGCAUCGCCCUCAACUUCCUGCACGAGAGGGGGAUCAUCUACAGGGACCUGAAGCUGGACAACGUCCUCCUGGAUGCGGACGGGCACAUCAAGCUCACAGACUACGGCAUGUGCAAGGAAGGCCUGGGCCCUGGUGACACAACGAGCACUUUCUGCGGAACCCCGAAUUACAUCGCCCCCGAAAUCCUGCGGGGAGAGGAGUACGGGUUCAGCGUGGACUGGUGGGCGCUGGGAGUCCUCAUGUUUGAGAUGAUGGCCGGGCGCUCCCCGUUCGACAUCAUCACCGACAACCCGGACAUGAACACAGAGGACUACCUUUUCCAAGUGAUCCUGGAGAAGCCCAUCCGGAUCCCCCGGUUCCUGUCCGUCAAAGCCUCCCAUGUUUUAAAAGGAUUUUUAAAUAAGGACCCCAAAGAGAGGCUCGGCUGCCGGCCACAGACUGGAUUUUCUGACAUCAAGUCCCACGCGUUCUUCCGCAGCAUAGACUGGGACUUGAUGCACAGACAACUCAGAUGCACAGACGCCCGGACGACGUGGACACCCAGACGAUGUGGACGCACAGACGACAUGGACGCACAGACGAUGUGGAUGCACGGACGACGUAGACACACGGAUGACUCAUCCACAGAUGACUCAGAUGCACGGACACCCAGACGACGCGGACGCACAGACGACGCGGACGCACAGAUGACGUGGACGCACAGAUGACGUGGACGCACGGACGACGUGGAUGCAUGGACGACGUGGACGCACAGAUGACCUGGACGCACGGACGACGUGGACGCACGGAUGACUCAGAUCCCCAGACGACUCAGAUGCACGGACACCCAGAUGACAUGGAUGCACGGACGACUCAGAUCCACAGAUGACUCAAACGCACAGAUGACUGGGAUGCUCAGAUGACCGCUGCUGUGCUGCCACCCCAGGGCUCUCUGGGCGUUUCCUGUGGUUUGGGCACCAGGAGCCUGGGAGUCCCAUGCUGCCCCCAGGGCACUACCUCCUGGGCCCAGCCCUGCAUCCGGUGGCAGGGCUCACCGUCAUCACCCCAACAGUGCAGGGUGGUCUCAGGGACCUCCUCUCAUCAUUGCCAAGAACUGGCUCCAGGAUGUUUCCAUGUGGCCGGCUAGUAUGGCCAAAGUGGACCCUGGCGUGCUGUCCCCUUGGACGCCUCCAGGCCCUGCCCAGCACGUGGGGCUCGUCCAUUCUGUGCCUGACCAUGCUCUGCCAUGCGGGGCCUAGCCCAGCCCCCCAGCCCUGCUGCUUCUCCCCACCCCACCCCCGCCACCUCCACCAAGCCACCAGCAUCCUGCCUGGCCCUACGGACAGCAGGGUCGUCCUGUGUCCAAAAGCCUCCUCCCCCUCAGCCCCUUCACUCGGGUCUCAUGGGGCCCCUCUGUGGCCCCCAGCGCACAAGGCACACACCCACUAUGGGGCCUUUGCACAGCUGUGCCCUCCCCAGGCUCCAGCCCUCACCUCCCCCAGGCUAUUUCUCAGAUGUCCCUUCAGAACUAGAGCCCUUGGGCCCCCAGCCCCAUUGACACGGAACGGGCCCCCUGUUGUAUCUCAGGUCACUGCUGUGGUUGCAGCCACAGGGGCAACACCUGUUACUGCCACAGCGUCCGACCUGGGGCCAGCGUGCAUUCAAACGCACUGCUCUGAGAGGCCAGGACGUCCAUGGGUUGGGCGCAGGGGGCGGCGGUGGGAAAAGGUGUCAGGCACCAUGGGUCCCGACCUGGAGCCCACGUGCCAGCUGCAGAGAUGGGCACUGAAGGCUUUUGAGCAAGAGGAGGAGGUAACGCUGGCCCCUGGGGAUGCUGUCAGGGAAACUGAGGCAAUCUUGAGCCCUCGGAGCAGAGAACGGGCUGGGCCAGGGGCUGGAGGACCCUGGGCCAGCUCCAGCUGGGUCCUGCUCUGUUCCCACCCCUGCUGCUUAUUAAACCCUUGUAAAGCAGCACAGGACUAAGGUAGGGAAAGUACUUUAGGAAAUGCCCCUUUUUCACAUUUUAUCGGCAGGUGUUUCAUACAAAGAAUACAAGUAACUGAUGAAUGAAGGGGGCAUCUUGUGUCCCCACAAUCCUGCUGUGCGCACACCACAG